GAGCUGGGCUGGCUUCCGUCCUGGUAGCCAAGGCUAAUUCUCCCUCGAGUUCUUGGGAGAUGGGCAUUUGGCGAGAAGGCUGGCGUUAGUGAAGCGCGCCCGGCGUCACGGUGAGUGCGGGUCUUGGGCCCUAGCACCUGUUCUCUGGGAAGUCGUCCGCUGUGAACGAUGAACGCCUUUCCUUCCACCAGCUGCUGGUUACCCCGGAGACAAGCUCUGUCCGCGGAGAGGAGUGGGACAACUCCUAAAGGAAAGAAGCACUUGUAAGGAAAUAUAGCAUCCAUUGUGAAAGUGGAAAAGUAAAGAUAAUUCAUCAUGCCUGCUGUGGCUUCAGUUCCUAAAGAACUCUACCUCAGUUCUUCACUAAAAGACCUUAAUAAGAAGACAGAAGUUAAACCAGAGAAAAUAAGCACUAAGAGUUAUGUGCACAGUGCCCUGAAGAUCUUUAAGACAGCAGAAGAAUGCAGAUUAGAUCGUGAUGAGGAAAGGGCCUAUGUACUAUAUAUGAAAUACGUGACUGUUUAUAAUCUUAUCAAAAAAAGACCUGAUUUCAAGCAACAGCAGGAUUAUUUCCAUUCAAUACUUGGACCUGGAAACAUCAAAAAAGCUGUCGAAGAAGCUGAAAGACUCUCUGAAAGCCUUAAAUUAAGAUAUGAAGAAGCUGAAGUCCGGAAAAAACUUGAGGAAAAAGACAGGCAGGAGGAAGCACAGCGGCUACAACAAAAAAGGCAGGAAACAGGAAGAGAGGAUGGUGGCACAUUGGCUAAAGGCUCUUUGGAGAAUGUUUUGGAUUCCAAAGACAAAACCCAAAAGAGCAAUGGUGAAAAGAAUGAAAAAUGUGAGACCAAAGAGAAAGGAGCAAUCACAGCAAAGGAACUAUACACAAUGAUGACGGAUAAAAACAUCAGCUUGAUUAUAAUGGAUGCUCGAAGAAUGCAGGAUUAUCAGGAUUCCUGUAUUUUACAUUCUCUCAGUGUUCCUGAAGAAGCCAUCAGUCCAGGAGUCACUGCUAGUUGGAUUGAAGCACACCUGCCAGAUGAUUCUAAAGACACAUGGAAGAAGAGGGGGAAUGUGGAGUAUGUGGUACUUCUUGACUGGUUUAGUUCUGCCAAAGAUUUACAGAUUGGAACAACUCUCCGGAGUCUGAAAGAUGCACUUUUCAAGUGGGAAAGUAAAACUGUCCUGCGCAAUGAGCCUUUGGUUUUAGAGGGAGGCUAUGAAAACUGGCUCCUUUGUUAUCCCCAGUAUACAACAAAUGCUAAGGUCACUCCACCCCCACGACGCCAGAAUGAAGAGGUGUCUAUCUCAUUGGAUUUUACUUAUCCCUCAUUGGAAGAAUCAAUUCCUUCUAAACCUGCUGCCCAGACGCCACCUGCAUCUAUAGAAGUAGAUGAAAAUAUAGAAUUGAUAAGUGGUCAAAAUGAGAGAAUGGGACCACUGAAUAUAUCAACUCCAGUUGAACCAGUUGCUGCUUCUAAAUCUGAUGUUUCACCCAUAAUUCAGCCAGUGCCUAGUAUAAAGAAUGUUCCACAGAUUGAUCGUACUAAAAAACCAGCAGUCAAAUUGCCUGAAGAGCAUAGAAUAAAAUCUGAAAGUACAAACCAUGAGCAACAAUCUCCUCAGAGUGGAAAAGUUAUUCCUGAUCGUUCCACCAAGCCAGUAGUUUUUUCUCCAACUCUCAUGUUAACAGAUGAAGAAAAGGCUCGUAUUCAUGCAGAAACUGCUCUUCUAAUGGAAAAAAACAAACAAGAAAAAGAACUUCGGGAAAGGCAGCAAGAGGAACAGAAAGAGAAACUGAGGAAGGAAGAACAAGAACAAAAAGCCAAAAAGAAACAAGAAGCUGAAGAAAAUGAAAUUACAGAGAAGCAACAAAAAGCAAAAGAAGAAAUGGAGAAGAAAGAAAGUGAACAGGCCAAGAAAGAAGAUAAAGAAACCUCAGCAAAGAGGGGCAAAGAAAUAACAGGAGUAAAAAGACAAAGUAAAAGUGAACAUGAAACUUCUGAUGCCAAGAAAUCUGUAGAAGAUAGGGGGAAAAGGUGUCCAACCCCAGAAAUACAGAAAAAGUCAACAGGAGAUGUGCCCCAUACAUCUGUGACAGGGGAUUCAGGUUCAGGCAAGCCAUUUAAGAUUAAAGGACAACCAGAAAGUGGAAUUCUAAGGACAGGAACUUUUAGAGAGGAUACAGACGAUACCGAAAGAAAUAAAGCUCAACGAGAACCUUUGACAAGAGCACGAAGUGAAGAAAUGGGGAGGAUCGUACCAGGACUGCCUUCAGGCUGGGCCAAGUUUCUUGACCCAAUCACUGGAACCUUUCGUUAUUAUCAUUCACCCACCAACACUGUUCAUAUGUACCCACCGGAAAUGGCUCCUUCAUCUGCACCUCCUUCCACCCCUCCAACUCAUAAAGCCAAGCCACAGAUUCCUGCUGAGCGGGAUAGGGAACCUUCCAAACUGAAGCGCUCCUACUCCUCCCCAGAUAUAACCCAGGCUAUUCAAGAGGAAGAGAAGAGGAAGCCAACAGUAACUCCAACAGUUAAUCGGGAAAACAAGCCAACAUGUUAUCCUAAAGCUGAGAUCUCAAGGCUUUCUGCUUCUCAGAUUCGGAACCUCAAUCCUGUUUUUGGAGGUUCUGGACCAGCUCUUACUGGACUUCGUAACUUAGGAAAUACUUGUUAUAUGAACUCAAUAUUGCAGUGCCUAUGUAACGCUCCACAUUUGGCUGAUUAUUUCAACCGAAACUGUUAUCAGGAUGAUAUUAACAGGUCAAAUUUGUUGGGGCAUAAAGGUGAAGUGGCAGAAGAAUUUGGUAUAAUCAUGAAAGCCCUGUGGACAGGACAGUAUAGAUAUAUCAGUCCAAAGGACUUUAAAAUCACCAUUGGGAAGAUCAAUGACCAGUUUGCAGGAUACAGUCAGCAAGAUUCACAAGAAUUGCUUCUGUUCCUAAUGGAUGGUCUCCAUGAAGAUCUAAAUAAAGCUGAUAAUCGGAAGAGAUAUAAAGAAGAAAAUAAUGAUCAUCUCGAUGACUUUAAAGCUGCAGAACAUGCCUGGCAGAAACACAAGCAGCUCAAUGAGUCUAUUAUUGUUGCACUUUUUCAGGGUCAAUUCAAAUCUACAGUACAGUGCCUCACAUGUCACAAAAAGUCUAGGACAUUUGAGGCCUUCAUGUAUUUGUCUCUACCACUAGCAUCCACAAGUAAAUGUACAUUACAGGAUUGCCUUAGAUUAUUUUCCAAAGAAGAAAAACUCACAGAUAACAACAGAUUUUACUGCAGUCAUUGCAGAGCUCGACGGGAUUCUCUAAAAAAGAUAGAAAUCUGGAAGUUACCACCUGUGCUUUUAGUGCAUCUGAAACGUUUUUCCUACGAUGGCAGGUGGAAACAAAAAUUACAGACAUCUGUGGACUUCCCGUUAGAAAAUCUUGACUUGUCACAGUAUGUUAUUGGUCCAAAGAACAAUUUGAAGAAAUAUAAUUUGUUUUCUGUUUCAAAUCACUACGGUGGGCUGGAUGGAGGCCACUACACAGCCUAUUGUAAAAAUGCAGCAAGACAACGGUGGUUUAAGUUUGAUGAUCAUGAAGUUUCUGAUAUCUCCGUUUCUUCUGUGAAAUCUUCAGCAGCUUAUAUCCUCUUUUAUACUUCAUUGGGACCACGAGUAACUGAUGUAGCCACAUAAGGAGACAUAGGUUAUAAACUAGUUAUCUUUUAAAAGGCUCAGCAACACAACUCUUGAAAUGCUUAUCAGGAUAAUGGUAGCUAUAGCUGGCCAUUUAGAGGAAUUCUAGGACAGUGGGAGCUGUGUUACUAGCACUAUAUAAUUCCGGUCAGUGCUGACAAAUAACAUUUAACAAGUAUUGCAGUAAUCAUCACUUACAGGUACCAUUUAUUUCAAAACAACUUUUUUAGUCUGCUCCAAAGUUAAAAUAAUUAACUAGCUAAGCAUUAUUAUUCGACUGGUCUAAAAACUAUUGUUAUCUUUUUUUUUUCCUUUUCACUGUUAUGGCCUUUUCACAUUUCUAAAUCCCAUCUUGAUAUACUAUGAAUACUCUAGAAUGAUGUAAAGCAGAUAGGAAUGUAUGUGUACAUAUUUAUUGCAUACUUGCACAUCAAAUCGAUGUACAUAGUUUAACACGUGGUCCUUUUGUGAAACCUAGAACUCAGAGGAUUGCUUUUUUUCUUUCAGCCUAUUUUGAGUUAACUUCAGUGCUUUCUUAGGGAAAUGACAGGGCAAAGCAAUUUUUCUGUUGGCUUUGGGCUGUAUUUGUGCACUAAAUCUUUAUUCUAAAAAAAAAAAUGGAAACUUUAAUUUUUUUAAAACGAGAAUUUCAUUUACAGCUACAUUAAAAUCUUAAUGAGAAAAAUAAUUUAUAACCCUGUGGGUGUUCUGUCUUUAAUAUUGUAUUAUCAAAUAUAGGACAGUAAAACCAUAGAUUUUAUAUACACACGUGCUAUAUAAUAACACCCAGAGUCAUUCUUUCAAGACUAGUAUUCUCACAUAUUGAGAAUAUUCAUUCUAAAUAUUAAAGUAAAAAUGCCGGGAGUCAGGCAUGAUUGCAAAGUGAACUGCAUUAUAAACUACAUCUUUACAGAGUGAUGUAUUAAGAGGGUUAAAGGAGCUUAUAAUUUAUUUAACCGAGGGACUCAGUUGCUAUAUAUAUAGUCAGUAAAACACUCCAUAUAAAAAUAAGAUUCUAAAAGUGCUUCAGAAAGAGACCACCAUUAGCAGGCUCUCAGGGAGAAGAUGAAAGGAUGGGGUUCAAAUUGUGAAGCUGACAACUUUUCAUGUUUUACAAUUAGUCUAAGAGACCACUUCUUGGCUAAAUUAUUAUAUCAAAUAUAUUCAAAUCAUAUUCUUAAACUCAUCGAGCCAUUUGAACAAAAAUUAUUUUUGUUUAGCUUCAUGAGUAUCUUUGGAAAAUAAUUUGUUGAAUAUAUAUGAUUAUGAGAUAUUUUCUGAUAAACACUGAAUUUUGAAACCUGAACUCACUAUAUAAUUGCAGUGUUUUGAAGGCCUGCAUCCAUUAGCAUUGCAUUAUAUUCACACUGCCUUUUUUAGUGAACCAAGACCCAUCUUCUGGACGACAGAUUUAUCUUAAGAUGAAAGGUUGUAUAACAUGCCCACAAGGCAUAAAAAUGUUAAUGAUGCAAGUAAGUUCUAAGAGUUUAAUGACCAAGCAAAACUCUACCACCAGAUGCUGACUGCUUGUUUUGCAGUGUUCAGGAAACACCAUUUUCCUGGCUCUUAACGCUUUUGUAUUGGUAUGGAAAAGGGCUGGCAGCUAUAGAACAGGAGAUCCAUAGCAUUUUGAACAGAAGUAUCUGGAAUCUCACUGACUCGUGUGUUAUCAAAGCUAUAUCAGGCCUGGGUGACUGAAUUCUUGCAGAAAGCAGUGUAGUGGCCACCAUCCAAAUCACCAAAAUGGUUCUAUGGGAGAAAGGAAUGUCAAACUUAGUAUUCACAUAUGAACACUAACUACUGGAACAGAAAUGAUAGGGCCAAGAGAUGCUUUUUAAAUUGUCCCUUAUUCUAAAUUAAAAGGAAGUGAUAAUUUUGUUGUUAAAUCAUGCAUAUAGCCUGACUGCUAUAUUGCUUCUCAUUUCAUUGUAACUACUUAUAUGUUGUGCCCAUUGACUAUCAUCUGUGAAUAAAGAAAGACAAUAUUUAGCAGCAUCUGAUUAAUGUUUAUCAGUGAACAUUUAGUUAGCACUUAAUAUACAUCAACUAUUAAGCAUUAAAGGAAAUUUUACAAUAAGAAGAUAAUUCAGGCCGGGCACAGUGGCUCACACCUGUAAUCCCAACACUCUGGGAGGCUGAGGCAGGUGGAUUGCUUGAGUCCAGGAGUUCAAGACCAGCCUGGGCAAAAUAGCGAGACUCCAUAUCUUUUAAAGGAAAAAAAAAAAAAAAAAAAAGAUGAGCUAGGCAUAGUGGUGCACACCUGUAGUCCCAGCUACUUGGGAAGUUGGGGUGGGAGGAUCUCUCGAGCCUGAGAGGUCGAGGCUGCAAUGAGCCGUGAUUGUACCACUGCACUCCAGCCUGGGUGACAGAGUGAGACCCUGUCUUAAAAUUGUAAGUUCAUUUACGUAAGAUGGCUUCUUUUUUUUUUUUUUAAAGUUAGGAUAAGCCACAGAAGAGACAUUUAACAUUAGAAUAAGGAUCUUAACUGCAUAUUGCUACAGCACAAAUUGAGGGGGCUAUGUAGCAACAACCCCUCAAUCCCCCAUAGGGUACAAAAAAUAAUGUAUCUCAUUUUCCUUUUUCCAUGUCUUUCCUAACCCAGUAUUGUUUGGAACAAAGGCAUUAGAGAGGUGUACUUCCAAGGAGGUGUUAUGGUGUAUGAUAAGGGUCAGCAAACCACGGCCCGUGGGUCAACUCCAGGCUGUUUUUGUAAGACCCAUGCAUUAGCAACGGGUUUUAAAUUUUUAUAUGGUUGGGGAAAAGAUCCAAGUAAUAAUAGUAUUGUUAUAUGUGAAAAUUUUAUGAAAUUCAAAUGUCAAUGUCCUUAAAGUUUUAUGGGAACACAGUCAUGCUCAUUUGUUUACACUUUUCAGUGGCUGCUUUAAUGAUACAACAGUAAAACUGAAUAGUUGCAGCCAAUACCAUAUGGCUUAUGAGGCCUAAAAUAUUUACUGUUUGGCCUUUAACAGAAUAAGUUUGCUGACCUCUGCUGUAGAGGAAGAAAAUUGAUUAUUUGUUAACUUAUUUUUAAUUUUUUGAGAUGGAGUCUCUCUCUGUUGCCCAGGCUGGAAUGCAGUGGCACGAUCUCGGCUCACUGCAACCUCCGCCUCCCAGGUUCAAGCAAUUCUUCUGCCUCAGCCUUCCAAGUAGCUGGGAGACUACAGGUGCCUGCCACCAUGCCCAGCUAAUUUUUUGUAUUUUUAGUAGAGAUGGGGUUUCACUGUGUUAGCCAGGAUGGUCUCGAUCUCGACCUCGGGAUCCUCCCACUUCGGCCUCCCAAAGUUAUUUAUUUUUAUUUGAGACAGAGUCUUGCUCUGUUGCCCAGGCUGGAGUGCAGUGACGUGAUCUCAGCUCACCACAACCUCUGCUUCCUGGGUUAAAGCUCUUCUCCUGCCUCAGCCUCCCAAGUAACUGGGAUUACAGGCACGCACCACCACACCCAGCUAAUUUUUUGUAUUUUUAGUAGAGAUGGGGUUUCGCCGUGUUGGCCAGGCUGGUCUUGAACUCCUGACCUCAAGUGAUCCACCUGCCUCCACCUCCCAAAGUGCUGGGAUUACAGGCGUGAGCCACUGCACCCAGCCUAUUUAUUUUUAGAAGCAGUUUCUUGCUAUGUUGCCCAGGCUGUACAUGAAUUCCUAGGCACAAGCAGUCCUCUCACUUCAGGCCCCCAAAUAGCUGGGACUACAGGCAUACACCACCAUGUCCAGAAUGAAAAUGGAUCUGACUAGUUAAUUCCAACGUGAAUUCGGGUGUAAUAGUACAUUGUGACCUUAGCGAAAUUAUUUGACCUUUCUGAGCUUUAAUUUCUCAUCUAUUAACAUGGCUUGUUUUGUAUAGCUGUUAUCAAAUAUCUCAUGUAUUGAGGGCUAGUACACAGGAGUUAUUUAUUCAAUAUUCCCUUCAACCUUCGUCUUCCCCACCUCUCUCCUUACAGGUAAUAGAAAUAUCUGAAAUUCACAUUUAAAAGAUCAAGGUUCCGCCAGGCCUGGUGGCUCACGCCUGUAAUCCCAGCACUUUGGGAGGCUGAGGCAGGCGGAUCACUUGAGGUCAGGAGUUUGAGACUAGCCUGGCCAACAUGGUGAAAAUCCAUCUCUUCUAAAAAUAUAAAAAUUAGCUGGGCAUGGUGGCGCAUGCCGGUAAUCCCAGCUACUUGGGAGGCUGAGGCAGAAUCAUUUGAACCUGGGAGAUGGAGGUUGCAGUGAGCUGAGAUCAUGCCAUUGCAUUCCAGCCUGGGCGGAGCCCUAAACAGGAAAUUUAACAACAGUAUGGUGUGUGGUUUAUGCUUUGUGACUGCCUGGGCGUAAAGACAGUCCCUAGUUUCUGUAACCAGUAUGCUCGGGUUUUAAAGGUCACGCAAGGACACUCGAGGUAAAGUCUUAGGCCCCCCUACAAGGUGAGAAGUUGGAUUGAGAUCCACAUACAAAGCCAGGACCUUUAAAGACAUUCACCCUCAAUGGAAGGAUUAAAAAACAAAAUCCACCCUCUAGUGCUUGUGUUAGCUUGGACUCAUGGUACAGAGAAUAAAAGUCAUUCCUGGGAAUUUGUCACCAUAGACCUACCUUUUCACCAGUUUGGGAUUCAAAUUUAUACUACCUGUGUGGUCUGCGAAUCCUGUGAACUUAAUAUGAAAAGUAUUUCUAGGGCAGUUGCCAGAAGGAAACAGAAUUUCUAGAUUGUUGCAUGUUAACUCAGACCUAACAGGAUAUCCACAUAUGAAACCCCAAUGAAGUUGAGAUCACAAUUCAAAAUAAUAGAACAUGCAAGGAAACAAUUUAUCAUAAGAGUCAGAAGGCAAUAAGAUUUAAACCCCCAAGGACUUUAGAUAAUAGAAUUAUUAAGCAGAGGCUACAAAUAAAGUAUAUUUAAAUAUAUUUAGAAGAAGGAAACAAACUUUAGAAACUAAAUAGAAUUUUCAGAAAUGAGAAAUACAACAUAGUUGGCCGUCCAUAUUUACGGGCUCUGCAUCUUCAGAAUCAACUAAUGUGAUGGGAAAGAUUUGAAAAAAUAAUACAACAAUAAAAAUAUACAUAUUUUAAAAUACAGUGUAACAACUAUUUACAUAGUAUUUAUAUUGUAUUAGAUAUUAUAAGUAAUCCAGAGAUGACUUAAAGUAUAUGGGAGGAUGUGCAUAGGUUACAUGCAAAUACUACUCCAGGCCUGGCAUGGUGGCUCACACGUGUAAUCCCAACGUUUUUGGGGGAUGGAGGUGGGCAGACUGCUUGAGCCCAGGAGUUGUAGACCAGCCUGGGCAACAUGGCAAAACCCUGUCUACACAAAAUACAAAAAUUGACCAGGCAUAGUGGCACGUGCCUAUAGUCCCAGCUACUUGGUAGGUUGAGGUGGGAGAAUCACCUGAGCCCAGGAGGUCGAGGCUACAGUGAGCUGUGACUGAGCCACUGCUCUCCAGCCUGGCAACAGAAUGAGACCUUGUCUCAAAAAACAAAAACAAAAAACACCAGAAAAGACACCAUUUUAUAUAGGGCCCUUGAGCAUCUGUGGAUUUUGAUAGUCAAAGGGAUCCUGGAACCAACUCCCUGCAGAUACUGAGGUACAACUGUACUGGAAAUUAACUUAAUGAAGAUAUUAGGACACAGAAAAUGAAUAAACCGGACUGGGCGCGGUGGCUCAUGCCUGUAAUCCUAGCACUUUGGGAGGCUGAGGCGGGUGGACCAUGAGGUCAGGAGUUCAAGACCAACCUGGUACACAUGGUGAAACCCUGUCUCUAUUAAAAAAAACAAAAAAAAUUAGCUGGGCCUGGUGGCGUGCACCUGUAAUCCCAGCUACUUGAGAGGCUGAAGCAGGAGAAUCGCUUGAACCCGGGAGGUGGAGGUUGCAGUGAGCCAAGAUCGUGCCAUUGCACUCCAGUGUGGGUGACAGAGUGAGACUCCAUCUCAAAAAAAAAAAAAAAAGAAUAAACUAUAAAAUGAAGUUGGGGAAAUUAGCAAGAAUGGAGUAGUGAUGGAGAAUACGUGUUAAGAGGCAUGAAAAAUUGAAUGAGAAUAUUCAGCGUAUGUCCUGUAGAAGUUCUAGGAGGAGAGAAUCGAGUAGGGGAGCAAGGCAAUAUUAAAAGUGAUAAUGGCUGAAAAUGAUUAAUGAGACAUGAAUCUUCACAUUUAGGAAAUGCAGCGAGCCAGGGAUAAAUAAAAAUAAUACUGCAGAACAACAGAGACAAAGAGAAAAAGCUUAAAAGCAACCAGAAAGAAAAAGAGAGUUUACCCACAAGAAUCUAACCUGCUGGUAGAAGUUCUCCAUAGCAGCCAUAGAAAUCAGAGACAAUACAGUAGCUUCAAAAUAAUAGAGAAAAAUAACUGUCAAUCUGGAAUUUGAUUUCUAGUUAUCAUCCAAGAAUGAAAGUGAAUUAAAGACUUCUCAAAGACUGAGAGACUUCAGGAUAACAGACCCUCACUGAAAAGCCUACUGAAAUAUAUGCCACAUGAAUUUUAAAAACUCAAUGAAGGAAGAAGUGAUACAUAAUAGACAGUGAUUAACAAAAAAGACUGAUGAAGAUCCGGGCAAAUAUAACCCAAUAUGAACAGUAGAAAACCAUGAUAAUGUCUCCUUUGGAGGCAUAUUAAAAAAUUAAAAACCGGCUGGGCAUGGUGGUUCACACCUGUAAUCCCAGCACUUUGGAAGGCCAAGGCAGGAGGAUCGUUUGAGCCCAGGAGUUUGAGACCAGCCUGGGCAACAUAGUGAGACCUGGUCUCUAAAAAAAAUAAAAAAGUUGGCCAUGCACAGUAGCAUGCCUGUAGUCCCAGCUACUUGGCAGGCAGAGGCAGGAGGAUCCCUUAAGCCCAGAGUUCAAAACUGUAGUGAGCUAUGAUUCAUUGCACUAGUGCACUCCAGUCUGGGCAACAGAGUGAGACCCUGUCUCAAAAACAAAAGAUGCUGAAAACAGUAGUUCAGUGAUCAGAAUUACAGUGUUCUAAGAGCUUUCCAUUUCUUUGGGAGCAGAGUAUAAAGAUCUUGAUUAACUUUAGGCUUUAAGUAUGAAAGCUGUCGUUUUUUAGCAUAAUUACUAAAGAAUCAAAAUGUGUAACUUCCAAAGUUGUAGAGGGAAAAUAAAGAAAGCUUUAUCAGUUUAGUAGCAGCAAGAACAACAGGGGAAAACAACACAGCAGAGGUCCCCAACCCCCCCAGGCUGCCUGUCCCUGACCUGUUCAGGACCUGGCUGCACAGCAGGAAGCGAGCGGCAAACCUACCCUGAGCACCGCCUCCUGUCAGAUCAGCUGCUGCAUUAGAUUCUCACAGCAGCACAAACUCUAUUGUGAACUGCGCAUGUGAGGGAUCUAGGUUGCGUGCUCCUUAUGAGAAUCUACUGCCUGAUUUUCUGAGGUGGAACAGUUUAAUCCCAAAACCAUGCCCGCCCCGGCCCCCAUCCAUGGGAAAAAAACCGCAUCAGUGGAAAAAUUGUCUUCCACAAAAAUCAGUCCCUGGUGCCAACAAGGUUGGGGACUGCCGAAUUAGAAAAAUAAGGCUAACAUAAACACAAAAGAAGAUGACGACAAGUAAAUCCGAAUUUAUUACUAGUUGAAAUAUAUGGGAUGUAGUAAAUUUACCAAAUAUUUACUGGAUUUUAAAUAUCCAGUUCUAGCCAGGCGCGAUGGCUCACGUCUAUAAUCUCAGCACUUGGGGAGGCCGAGGGGGGCGGAUCACGAGGUCAGGAGAUCAAGACUAUCCUGGCCAACACGGUGAAACCUCAUCUCUACAAAAAUACAAAAAAUUAGCCGGGCAUGGUGGCAGGCGCCUAUAGUCCCAGCUACUCCGGAGGCUGAGGCAGGAGAAUGGCAUGAACCCAGGAGGUGAAGCUUGCAGUGAGCCGAGAUCGUGCCACUGCAUUCCAGCCUGGGCGACAGAGCGAGACUUCAUCUCAAAAAAAAAAAAAAAAAAAAAAAAAAAAAAAAAUCCAGUUUUAGGCCAAGUGUGGUGGCUCAUGCCUGUAAUCCCAACACUUUGGGAGGCCAAGGCAGGCGGAUCACCUGAGAUCAGGAGUUCCAGACCACCCUGGCCAACAUGGCAAAACCCGGUCUCUACUAAAAAUACAAAAAUUAGCUGGGUCUGGUGGCACAUGCCAGUAAUCCCAACUACUUGGGAAGCUGAGGCAGGAGAGUUGCUUGAACCUGGGAGGUGGAGGUUGCAGUGAGCCAAGAUCAUGCCACUGCACUCCAGCCUGGGGCACAGAGUGAGACUCUGUCUCUAAAACAAAACAACAACAACAACAAAUCCAGUUCUAUGCACUAUAUAACAUUUAGAACUCAGAAAAGGUGUAUUUCCCUUGAGCAUCAUGUUGGUGCUUAAAAUGUUUCAGAUUUUGGAGCAUUUUGGAUUUUCAGAUUAGGGAUGCUCAACUUGUCGUAGGUAGAUAUGACCAAGAGAAAGCUGAAGUAGCUAUACAUCAGCUAAAAUGGUCCCUAAGAUAGAAUGCAUUGUAAAUGAGUCACUUUAUAAUGAAAAAAGGUUUAAAUCACCCAAAUUGUAUAAUUUGAAACUGCUACCUACCUAACAAAACAGACUUGUUAAAAACAAAUGACAGAACUAUAGGGAAGUUUUGACAAGUCUACCAUCAUAAUGGAAGAUUUCAACUAUUGAUCAAGCAGACAAAAAUAUUAGUAUAGAUACAGCUUUUACAAUAUAUACUUAGAUGAGUAUCUGACUCCUGAAAUAGAAGUGCACUGUCUCAACAAAUGUAAAAGAGUUAGUUUAGGCCAGGCACGGUGGCUCAUGCCUGUAAUCCCAGCACUUUGGGAGGCCAAGGCAGGCGAAUCACGAGGUCAGGAGUUCGAGACCAGCCUGGCCAACAUGGAGAAACCCCGUCUCUACUAAAAAUACAAAAAAUUAGCUGGGCAUGGUGUCGGCUGCCUGUAAUCCCAGCUACUGAGGAGGCUGAAGCAGGAAAAUCGCUUGAAACUGGGCGGCGGAGGUUGCAGUGAGCCGAGAUGGUGCCAGUGCACUCUAGCCCGGGCGACAGUGCAAGACUCUGUCUCAAAAAAAAAAAAAAAAAAAAAAAAAGAUUAGUUUAAUUUAGACCCUAGUCUUUGAACACAAUACAAUUAGCAGUCAAUACAAAAUGAUACCCCCACAAAAAAUCAAUACUUUUGGAAAUUAAAAAAACACUUCUAAGUAACUUUAUAAAUAAAUUAUAAAAGUAAAACACUUAGAAGUAAAUAGUAAUGAAAAUACUAUAUCAAAACAUGGGAUGCACUGAUGUCUGAGAAUGUCUUAAAAAUAAUACGAUGCCAAGAAGAGAGUGGGUCAGUAUUAAGAUGAAUUGAUCAUUUAUUUUAUAUUCAAAUAUCUUGCUUCAGCAAGCUAGUUGAUGGAUGCAUGGCGGUUUGUUAUGCUGUCCAAUUUUGUAUAUGUUUGAAAUAUUCUAUAAUAAAAAAAGGCAGAGAAAGUGGGAGAUAGACAUUUGUAGUUUUAAAUACUUAUAUCUUAAAGGAUAGACUGAGUGUUAAUACACUGGACACUCAGUUUAAAACAUUAAAACAUAACAGAAUAAACCCUAAAAGAGUAGAGGGAAGAGAUAACACUGUAAGAGGAAUAACCCAUAAAGCAGAAAACAAAGAUGUAAUACAGAAGAUUUAAAAAAAGGUAAAAGUUGGUGUUUUAAGACAAAAUAAUUUGGAUGUUAGCCUGCCACAGUGGUUCAUGCCUAUAAUCCCUGCACUUUGGGAGGCCAAGGCAGAUGGAUCGCCUGAGUCCAGGAGUUUGAAACCAGCUUGGGCAACAUGGCAAAACCCCGUCUCUAUAAAAAAAAAAAGAGUACAGGCCAGGCGCGGUGGCUCACGCCUGUAAUCCCAGCACUUUGGGAGGCCGAGGCGGGCGGAUCACGAGGUCAGGAGAUUGAGACCAUCCUGGCUAACACGGUGAAACCCCAUCUCUAUUAAAAAUACAAAAAAUUACCUGGGCACGGUGGCGGGCGCCUGUAGUCCCAGCUACUUGGGAGGCUGAGGCAGGAGAAUGGCGUGAACCCGGGGUCGGAGCUUGCAGUGAGCCAAGAUCGCGCCACUGUGCUCCAGCCUGGGCGACAGAGCGAGACUCCGUCACAAAAAAAAAAAAAAAAAAAAAAAAAAAAAUUACAAAAUUAGCUGGACAUGGUGUUGUGCCUGUAGUUCCAUCUACUUGGGAGGCUGAGGUGGGAGGAUGGCUCGAGCCUGGGAGGCAGAGGUUGCAGUGAGCCAAGAUCACACCACUGCACUCCAGCCUGGGAGACAGAGUGAGACCCUCUCUCAAAAAUAGUAACUUGGACGUCAAUAGUAAGAUUUAGAGAAUAAGAGACAAGGCGGCCGGGCGCGGUGGCUCAUGUAAUCCCAGCACUUUGGAAGGCUGAGGCAGGCGGAUCACCAGGUCAGGAAAUUGAGACUAUCCUGGCUAACACGGUGAAACACCGUCUCUACUAAAAAUACAAAAAAUUAGCCGGGCAUGGUGGCGGGCGCCUGUAGUCCCAAGCUACUCAGGAGGCUGAGACAGGAGAAUGACUUGAACCCGGGAGGCGGAGCUUGCCGUGAGCUGAGAUCGUGCCAUUGCACUCCAGCCUGGGCGACAGAGCGAGACUGCGUCUCAAAAAAUAAAAUAAAAUAAAAUAAAAUAAAAAAGAGACAAGUCAACGAUAAAAUUAAAAAUGAAAAAACAUGUAAUAGCUACAGAUCCUGAAUAAAUUUAUUGUUAAUACCCUAAAAACUUUAUGCCAGCCAACUGAGACCUUAGAUGAAAUAGACAAAUAUCUGGAGAAUAAGUUACCAAAAUGACUGAAGAGAAAUACAUGGCUCACACCUAUAUUUUUUACAGAAAUUGACAAGGGCCAGGAAUAAUCGAAAUACUACUGAAAAAUAAGAAUAAAGUUGUGAUGGUAAUGACUUAGGGAAUAAUGAUGGUUCUUGCUCUGCCAGAUAUCAAUGUUUAUUUCAAAGCUAUAGCUAUAAUUAAUAUUCAUAAGCUAAAUUAAGAAUUAAUUCAAUAUUAAUUUAAUAAAUUUAAUAUUUUAUAGCUAUAAUUAAUACAGUACGGAAUUAGCCCAAAUGUGAACAAAUUGACCAACAGACACACACAGCAUAGGAAAACCAGCAUUAUAUGUUACUGAGGAAAAGAAGAGGCUGAGACAUUUGGUUAUUCAUAUGCAGAAAAAUGAAAUUGAAUCCCUAAUUUAUACUACAUUUUUGUCAGAAGUGCAAAACAAUUUAAAUGUUUGGAAGAUAUGUAGGUAAAUAUCUUUGUAAUUCCAGGGUUGGAAAGGAUUUCUUAAAUGAGACACAGAAAAGGACUAACUAGAAAAGAUUGAUGUUCCAACCAAAUUAAAACUUGAUUGUCAGCAAUUACAAUAAGAUACAACAACCAAAUGCAGUUUGUGAAUUUUGGAUGGAUUCUGGUCUUUGAAAAAAAAUGCUACUAAAAAAAAAAACCUUGUGACAAUUGAUAUUUGAAUAUGAAUCUAUGAAUAUGAGUGAUGGAAUUUUAAAUUUUCUUACAUAUAAUUCUGCUAUUGUGGGUAUGUAGAAGAAUGUGGUUAAGGGAUUAUUUUGAUCUAUGAAGUGUCACGAUACAAGAUUUAAAUCAGCAAAAAGUUAGAUAUACGUGUGUAUAGAUGUGCACAUAUAUAUGUAUAGAGAGUGAAAGUAAUAAAAGUGUAUACACUGCUAAAUGUUAAUAACUGAAUCUAGCUGAAAUGUACACCAAUGUACACCAAUGUUUUGUUUUUUGGUUUUUUUUUUAGAGAUGGAGUCUCGCUCUGUCUCCCAGGCUGGAGUGCAGUGGCGCUAUCUCGGCUCACUGCAAGCUCCGCCUCCUGGGUUCACGCCAUUCUCCUGCCUCAGCCUCCUGAGUAGCUGGGACUACAGGCGCCCGCCACCAUGCCCGGCUAAUUUUUUUUGUAUUUUUAGUAGAGACGGGGUUUCACCGUGUUAGCCAGGAUGGUCUCGAUCUCCUGACCUCGUGAUCCGCCUGCCUUGGCCUCCCAAAGUGCUGGGAUUACAGGCGUCAGCCACCGUGCCCGGCCGAUGUACACCAAUGUUCUCUGUACAAUUCUUUCAGAUUUUCUGAAUGUUUGCAAAGUUUUAUUUUAAAAACUGGAGAGAGAGCACUUGAAAAGAUGCUCAACAUCAUUAGUCAUUAGGAAAAUGCAACUCAAAACCAUGACAUACCAGUUCAUACCUACUUUGUAUGGGAUAGAAUAAAAAAUGAGAGGCAGUAACAAGUUCGGUUGAGGAUGUGGGGAAACUGGAACCUUAGUUCCAGUUGCUGGUGGGAACGUAAAAUGCUGCUGCCACUUUGGAAAACAAUUUGGCAGUUCCUCAAAAAAUUAACCAGAGUUACCAUAUGACCCAGAAAUUUCACACUUAGGUAUAUACCCAACAGAAAUGAAAACAUGUUUACAGAAAAUCCUGUACAUAAAUGUUCAUAGCAGCAUUACUGAUGACAGCCAAAAGUGGAAACAAGCCAAAUGUCCAUCACUGGAUGGAUUAAGGAAAUGUGGUAUAUCCUAUACAAUGGAAUAUUAUUUGGCAAUAAAAAGGAAUGAAGUACAGAUACAUGCUAUGACAUGAAUGAAACUUGAAAACAUUAUGCUGAAUAAAAGAAAAUAAAAACAGAAGGUCAUAUAUUCUAUGAUUCUGUUUAUUAAAAUACCCAGAAUAGGCCAGGCACUGUGGCUCACGCCUGUAAUCCCAGCACCUGGGGGAGCCGAGGCAGGUGGAUCACUUGACGUCUGGAGUUUGAGACCAGCCUGGGCAAUAUAGCAAAACCCCAUCUCAACCAAAAUACACAAAAAUUAUUGGGGCAUGGUGGUGCACACCUGUGGUCCCAGCUACUCGAGGGAGGGAGGAGGGAAGAUCACUUGAGCCAGGGAGGUUGAGGCUGCAGUGAGCUGAGAUUGCACCAUUGCACUCCAGCCUGAGCAAGAGUGAGAUAUUGUCUCAAAAAAUAAAAUAAAUAAAAUUUUAAAAAUACGCAGAAUAGGCACAUCUAUAGAAAUAUAUAAAGUAGAGGCCAGGAGAAGUGGUUCAUGCCUGUAAUCCGAGCACUUUGGGAGGCCAAGGUGGGUGCGCCACUUGAGGUCAGGAGUUCAAGACCAGCCUGGUCAACAUGGUGAAACCCCACCUCUACUAAAAAUACAAAAAUACACCUGUAGUCCCAGCUACUCGGGAGGCUGAGUUACGAGAAUCCCUUGAACCUGGGAGGCGGAAGUUGCAGUGAGCUGAAAUCAUGCCACUGCACUCCAGCCUGGGCAACAGAGCAAGACUCUGUUAAAAAAAAAAAAAAUAGCGAGAGAUCGAGAGAGAGUGCACGUGAGAAGACUAGUAGUUGCUAUGGACUGGGGGAGAAGGAACGGGUUACAGGGUUUCUUUUGGGGAUAACGAAAAUGUUCUAAAACUGGACUGUGGUGAUAACUGCACAACUCUGUGAAUGUACUAAAAACUACUGAACUGGCCAGGCACAGUGGCUCACACCUGUAAUCCCAGCACUUUGGGAGGCCCUGAGAUGGGCAGAUCACUUGAGGUCAGGAGUUCCAGACCAGUCUGGCCAACAUGGUGAAACCACAUCUCUACUAAAAAUAUUUUUAAAAAUUAGCCAGGCAUGGUGGUGCACCUGUAAUCCCAGCUACUUGGGAGGCUGGGGCAUGAGAAUCAUUUGAAACCAGGGGGUGGAGGUUGCAGUGAGCCGAGAUCACACCACCGCACUCCAGCCUGGGCGACAGAGCCAGACUCUGUCUCAAAAACAAACAAAACAAAAACAACAAAAAACACAACUGAACACAUUUAAGGUGAAUUCUGUGGUAUGUGAACUAUCUCUAAGAACUUCUUUUUAUUUAAGUUGGGAAACAAAAAGAUCAUGUACAACAAACCAAAAACAAAAAAGUUAUUUCUAACCCAUGUAACAUAUAACAAGGAUCUAGAACAUGUAAAUGACUCUUUCCAAUCAAUAAGAAGAAAAAUAACCCAGUUUGUAAAAAAUGUGCAAAAGACAAAUAUUUCAUACAAUAGGAAAAACUAAAAUGAGAUAAUUUUGUAUCCAUUAGAUGGCAAAAAUUAAGAAGUCUGAUGAUCCUGGUAGGGGUAUGUAUUGGUAUAAUCACUUGUAGAAAGUUAAAUAUGCACAUACUUUAUGAUCUAAGUGACCUCACUCCUAAGUAUAUACAUGAGAGAAACUCUUAUGCACAUAUAUAUGCAGGAAUGUCUGCAUAAUGUUGUUCAUGCCAGCAAAAAUUUGGAAACAAUGAAAUAUCAAUAGGAAAAUGGAUAAUUUAUGAUAUAUUCACACAAUAUACAUCAUAGGCUAGUGAAAUUAUAACCACAUGCAACAAUAUGGAUAUAUCUUUAAAAUAUUUAAUGAAAAAGUAUGCUUGGCGCGGUAGCUCACACCUGUAAUCCCAGCACUUUGGGAGGAUGAGGGAGGUGGAUCACCUGAGGUCAUGAGUUCGAGACAAGAGCGAAACUGUCUAAAAAAAAAAAAAAAAAAAAGAGUGAAGAAUCAAGCCACAGAAGGUAAUUUAAAAAUGUACACUCAAGAUUUAAAAAGAACUACAAUUCCAUAAGAAAAAGGCAGGCCACAGAAUAGGAAAAAGAAUAAAAGACUUGUUUAGGCAUUUCACAAAAGAAAGUAUACAAAUUUAAGUAGUUAUUUAAACCACAAUGCCAUUCUACUAUAUGGGCAACCAGAAGGGCCAAAACAAAACGAACAAAAGACUACCAAGUGUUAACAAGGAUUUAAGGCAACUGAAACUUCCAGUCAUUGCUGGUGGGGGUAUGAAUUGGUACAGUCGCUUUGGAAAGCUACUGAGCAGUAUGUACUAAAGCCAGACAUAUGCGUAUUUCUGAACCAGGAGUUUCACUCCUAGGUAUGUACUCAAAAGAACUGUGUACACUAUGUUCACCAAAAAACAAGAAUGUUUAUAGCAACCCUCUUUGCAUUAGUCAAAAGCUAGUAAUUACCCAAAAGUUCCUGAAUGGUAGAAUGAAUUACUAAAUUGUAGUAUUUUCAUACAAUGGAAUACUAUACAGCAAUGAGAAUGAAUAAAUUACAAUAUAAACAACAAUAUGGAUGAACAUUACAUAAUUUUGAAUGAAAGGAGCCAGACACAAAAAAAGGAUAUACUGUACAAUUCCAUUUAUACGAAGCAUAAAAUCAGGCAAAAAUCUAUAAAUCUGUCCUGCCAGAAGUCAGUGGUUUUCCAGACUCGAAGGCAGGUACAAGCACAGUUAGGGUGCUGGUAACAUUCUGUUUAAACUCUGUUCUGCUGGUUACAUGGGUAUGUUCACUUGAAAAUCCAUCAAGUUUUAUCCUCAUGGUUUGUGUACUUUUCUGUAUAUAUGUUUCACUUCAAUAAAGUUUAUUUUUGGUCAA